AAGUUACAUCCUCCAACAACAAAGCAAAUUAGACGGGAAAGCAGGAAAGCUGUGCAGAAAUUCUGACCUGAAACGCUUCGCAUCCGGUCUCUGCUUGUUGAAGGACCUUCACCGCUAUUUCUGAGAAGAGCAAAAGUGAUGCAGAUCUGUUCUUCCUCUUCUUAAUCCCAGAGAAGUUCCUAAUAAGCCAGUAAUGGCGCCUCCGCAGAGGCAUCCGCAGCGCAGCGAGCAGGUCCUGCUCCUCACGCUCCUGGGGACGCUGUGGGGGGCCGCGGCAGCGCAGAUCCGCUACUCUAUUCCCGAGGAGCUGGAGAAAGGCUCCUUCGUAGGCAACAUCGUCAAGGAUCUGGGACUGGAGCCCCAGGAGUUGGCGGAGCACGGAGUCCGCAUCGUCUCCAGAGGUAGGAUGCAGCUUUUCUCUCUGAAUCCGCGAAACGGCAGCUUGGUCACCGCGGGUAGGAUAGACCGCGAGGAGCUCUGUGCUCAGAGCCCGCGGUGUCUGGUGAGUUUUAACAUCCUUGUCGAGGAUAAACUGAAUCUUUAUCCCGUGGAAGUGGAAAUAGUGGACAUUAAUGACAAUACACCCCGAUUCUUAAAGGAAGAAUUGGAAGUGAAAAUUCUCGAAAACGCAGCUCCAUCCUCUCGUUUUCCACUAAUGGAGGUCUAUGACCCUGAUGUGGGAAUGAACUCCCUUCAGGGAUUUAAGCUCAGUGGUAAUAGUCACUUCUCAGUGGACGUGCAAAGCGAAGCCCAUGGGCCCAAGUACCCGGAGCUGGUGCUGGAGGGCACACUGGACCGGGAAGGAGAAGCCGUUUACCGCCUGGUCCUUACUGCCAUGGAUGGCGGCGACCCUGUCCGCUCAAGCGUCGCCCAAAUUCUGGUAACAGUUCUAGAUGUGAAUGACAACACUCCAAUGUUUACUCAGCCUGUCUACCGUGUAAGUGUUCCUGAAAACCUGCCAGUAGGCACACCAGUGUUGGCAGUGACUGCCACCGACCAGGAUGAAGGAGUCCACGGGGAAGUAACUUAUUCCUUUGUGAAGAUUACAGAAAAGAUCUCACAAAUUUUCUGUUUGAAUGUUUUGACUGGAGAAAUUUCAACUUCUGCAAAUCUAGACUAUGAGGACUCGAGUUUUUAUGAGCUGGGUGUUGAAGCCCGGGAUGGGCCAGGUCUUCGAGACAGAGCGAAAGUCUUAAUAACUAUCUUGGAUGUCAAUGAUAAUGUACCAGAAGUGGUUGUUACAUCUGGAAGCAGAACAAUUGCUGAAAGUGCACCUCCAGGAACAGUAAUCGCCCUUUUUCAAGUGUUCGAUCGAGACUCUGGCCUGAAUGGCCUGGUAACCUGUUCCAUCCCGAGAAGUCUCCCAUUUGAAUUGGAAAAAUCAGUUGGCAAUUAUUAUCGAUUAGUGACAAAUGCAGCUCUAGACCGGGAAGAGGUAUUCUUGUACAACAUCACUGUGACAGCCACGGACAAAGGAACACCACCUCUGUCUACAGAAACAAUCAUCUCUCUAAAUGUGGCAGACACCAACGACAACCCGCCCACCUUCCCCCAUUCAUCCUACUCAGUCUAUGUCCUUGAAAACAACCCCAGGGGUGCCUCCAUCUUCUCUGUGAAUGCACUGGACCCUGACGUGGACCAGAACGCCCAAGUCUCCUACUCACUGGCAGAAGACACCCUCCAGGGGGCGCCCCUGUCCUCCUACGUGUCCAUCAACUCCGACACUGGGAUUCUGUACGCCCUGCGCUCCUUCGACUAUGAGCAGUUGAGAGACCUACAGCUGUGGGUGACAGCCAGCGACAGCGGGGACCCGCCUCUUAGCAGCAACGUGUCACUGAGCCUGUUUGUGCUGGACCAGAAUGACAAUGCGCCCGAGAUCCUGUACCCCGCCCUCCCCACAGACGGUUCCACUGGCGUGGAGCUGGCGCCCCGCUCCGCAGAGCCCGGCUACCUGGUGACCAAGGUGGUGGCGGUGGACAGAGACUCGGGCCAGAACGCCUGGCUGUCCUACCGCCUGCUCAAGGCCAGCGAGCCAGGACUUUUCUCAGUGGGCCUGCACACGGGCGAGGUGCGCACGGCGCGCGCCCUGCUGGACAGAGACGCGCUCAAGCAGAGCCUAGUGGUGGCCGUCCAGGACCACGGCCAGCCCCCUCUCUCCGCCACUGUCACGCUCACCGUGGCCGUGGCCGACAGGAUCCCCGACAUCCUGGCCGACCUGGGCAGCCUCGAGCCCUCCGCCAAACCCAACGAUUCGGACCUCACUCUGUACCUGGUGGUGGCGGUGGCCGCGGUCUCCUGCGUCUUCCUGGCCUUCGUCAUCGUGCUGCUGGCGCUCAGACUGCAGCGCUGGCACAAGUCACGCCUGCUGCAGGCUUCGGGAGGUGGCUUAGCGAGCAUGCCCGGCUCGCACUUUGUGGGCGUGGAAGGGGUUCGGGCUUUCCUGCAGACCUAUUCCCACGAGGUCUCACUCACUGCAGACUCGCGUAAGAGUCAUCUGAUUUUCCCCCAGCCCAACUAUGCCGACACGCUUAUCAACCAGGAGAGCUAUGAGAAAAGCGAGCCUCUUCUGAUAACUCAGGAUUUACUUGAAACGAAAGGAGAACCCAGGCAACUUCAGGUGAGUUUCUUUCCGCCUAAGCGGGAAGAGUAAUCUGAUCUUCCCGCAACCCAACUAAUCAGACAGGCUCAUCAGCUAGAUCGGCUGUUAUAGAAGCGAACCUCUUUUGGUACAGGAAGAUUCGUGAUUUUGUAAAGUGGAAGACUCCCUUGUUCAGGUGAGGGUAUCGUUUUUUUUUUUUUUUUUUUUUGAGACGGAGUCUCGCUCUGUCGCCCAGGCCGGACUGCGGACUGCAGUGGCGCAAUCUCGGCUCACUGCAAGCUCCGCUUCCCGGGUUCACGCCAUUCUCCUGCCUCAGCCUCCCUAGUAGCUGGGACUACAGGCGCCCGCCACCGCGCCCGGCUAAUUUUUUUGUAUUUUUAGUAGAGACGGGGUUUCACCUUGUUAGCCAGGAUGGUCUCGAUCUCCUGACCUCAUGAUCCACCCGCCUCGGCCUCCCAAAGUGCUGGGAUUACAGGCGUGAGCCACCGCGCCCGGCCGAGGGUAUCGUUUUUAUUGGUUGACAGGAAAAUUCAAGAUUGUCUUUGAUUAGUGCUUAGUUUUCUUAGCCCUUUGCAGAGAGUCACAUAAUUCUAAUGUUUUUCUUUUAUAUCAAAAGAAUGUUCUGAAGUCUUAAUUUUGUGGGGGAAAAUAAUGCAUGUCCUAGUUUUUCUUUACCUUUCUCUUCUUGGCAAACUAUUUGUGUCUUGGAUUGAGUACAUCUCGUUUCUUAGGUUUUUUCCUACUAUGUGACAUUUGUAAGGUUCUUUCUUUUUCUAAUGUGGGAAAAAAAAUAACCUUAAUUUAGGUCAGUGUUAAAGAUCAAGAUCUUGGUUUUAGCUAGCAUGGUGGUUCACGCCUGUAAUCCCACCUCUUCAGGAGGCUGAGGCAGGAGGAUCCCUUGAGACCAGGAGUUUGAGACCAGCCUGGGUGACUCUGUCUCUACCAAAAAGAAAAAAAAGUAGCCAGAUGUGUGGCGUACACCUGUAGUCCCAGCUACUCGAGAAGCUCUGAUAGGAGGAUUGCUUAAGUCCAGGGGUAUGAGGCUGCAGUGAGAUAUAAUUGUGUCACUGCACCCUAGCCUGGGAGACAGAAUGAGACUUUUUCUCUCUCUCUCUCAAAAAAAAAAAAAGAUUUUGUUUUUUCUCAGUGUUACUUGAUAACUAUAAACGACAGACGUUCAUACAAGAGAUCUUUCACCUUUACUACUUAGGAAUCAAAAAUUAUUUUUGAAAAGAUAAGAAUCAUUGGUAACUGCAGCAGGGGACACCAGAUCUUUGGUGUUAAAAGACCUGAAUAACAUUCCUGUAACUAUCUGUUAUUUACUUGGGCCAGUUACAAUCGCCAUUAUCUUCCAAUUAAAAUUAAGAUUUAAAAGACUUCUCUUAUCAGAGAUAGGAUCCCCCUCUGUUGCCCAGUCUGGAGUAAAAAUCCACCUGUAACUGCUGCUUAUAGAGUGUGUAUCCAGGGCAACUUGAAUCUAUGUUCCUGGGUUGCAAUCCUAAAGCUUGGCUCAAAUAAGCUCUACUUAUAUUAUUUUUUAAAACAAGACUUUCCUUAUCUAUCUGACUCAAAUUCUAAGAAAAUAAUUUUAUAACUUUUUUUCAAACUCUAAAGCAGCAUAGUGAACACGUAUUUGUUGACAUCACCAUUAUUAUAAUUAUUGGGUUGUUAACAAUAACUAAGCACCGAUGCUGUGUGCCUACUACAGUGUCUUUUGCAUACUGUGUGCCUGAUAGUAUUUAAGAGUGAAAAUGGCCGGGUGCGGUGGCUCAUGCCUGUAAUCCCAACACUUUGGGAGGCCAAGGCAGGCAUCUCACGAAGUCAGGAGUUCGAGACCAGCCUGACCAACAUGGUGAAACCCCGUCUCUACUAAAAAUACAAAAAUUAGCCAGGUGGGGUGGCAUGGGCCUGUAAUCGCAGCUACUCGGGAGGCUGAGGCAGGAGAAUCGCUUGAACCCAUGAGGCAGAGGUUGCAGUGAGCCAAGAUCGUGCCACUGCACUCCAGUCUGGGUGACAGAGCGAGACUCUGUCUCAAAAAAUAAUAAUGAUAAUUAAUAAAUAAAGAGUGAACAUGAAUUUUAAAACAUGCUCGGUAGUGUCUGCUUACAGGACAUAUCUCUAAAAAUAGAUGACUGACUGGUGAAUGGGAGAACAAAUGUUAAUGAGGUUCAAAUAAAAAUUUAAAUAUUUUAGCAUUUUAACCCAGACAAUAAGGCUUUCAUCAUAUAGGAACUCUUUAUUGAAAUAUUUCAAGAAAAAAGGGAUUAUCAUUUAGAAGACUGAUUAGUCUUAUUUAUUAUGACUGAAAUGUGCAAACAGAAUCAUUGUUUCAUGAACAGAAAACAGCAGAGUUUUUGACUGUCAAUGAUGUUCGAAUAGAAAAUGGAUCACUAAGGAGAUAGGAGAUUCUGUUAUCGACAGUCUUCAAAAGUAAGUUGAUGGCCCUGGAAUGAAUGGAGUACAGGGGAUUCUCUAAUUUGAUGACUUGUUGAACUACAUUAUAGUCAAGAUUUUUCUCCAGUCAUGAGUUGGAAGAUUCUACAAUCUGGUGGUAUUAUAGAAUGGAUUGGCCACUUGUGCAUCUGAAUUUGUUAUGAAUGUGUAAGAAAAAAGCAAUUGAGAAGAUACCUUGAAAAUAAAUGAGAACCUCCUUUGUAACCUGACUUUGUCAGUCUUCUUAAAGAUAACAUUGAGUUGAUGUGUUUUUAAAUAAGCUGCUAAGAGUAAUAUGUGUUUUUCUGAACCAAUAUUGUGGUAUUUACAUUUAAGGAAUUGUUAUAGAUUUAUUUAUUUCAAGUUUCCAAAGGUAUAUACCUAAACAAGAGAUCUAAUCAUACACAUCUUCAAAGCUCAUUUUCUUGUAUCUUUGUGAUAUAAUUUGAUAAAAUAACAAUUUUAAACAACUUGAAUCUUGGAUAUUAGUCUCAUGAGUUAGAUGGGCUGUUAUACAUAUGAUUAUUUCAUAAACUCUGAAAGUGUGAAUGUUAUUUUACUAUACUACCAAUUUGGGAUGUUAAACUACAUCUUGAGCAUUUGUUGUUAUAGGGAAAGCUCACUAACUACUUUUCAUGGAGAUCAGGCUGGUUUAUUUUAUUCUCUUAUUACCUGUGACCAUUUCAUUUAAACAAAUAAAAUAUUUCUCUGAUGGAAAAACUA